AGUGUUCCUGCUGUCUGCUCAUCCGCUGACUGUGUUCACUCUUACCUGAGCAGGUUUCUGGGAUAAGUAUGUGCAAAUAAAAAAUAAACAUGAGAAGGAACUGUAACCUGAUUAUGGAUUUGGGAAAAAGAUAAAUCAACACACAAAGGGAAAAGUAAACUGAUUGACAGCCCUCAGGAAUGAUGCCCUUUUGCCACAAUAUAAUUAAUAUUUCCUGUGUGAAAAACAACUGGUCAAAUGAUGUCCGUGCUUCCCUGUACAGUUUAAUGGUGCUCAUAAUUCUGACCACACUCGUUGGCAAUCUGAUAGUUAUUGUUUCUAUAUCACACUUCAAACAACUUCAUACCCCAACAAAUUGGCUCAUUCAUUCCAUGGCCACUGUGGACUUUCUUCUGGGGUGUCUGGUCAUGCCUUACAGUAUGGUGAGAUCUGCUGAGCACUGUUGGUAUUUUGGAGAAGUCUUCUGUAAAAUUCACACAAGCACCGACAUUAUGCUGAGCUCAGCCUCCAUUUUCCAUUUGUCUUUCAUCUCCAUUGACCGCUACUAUGCUGUGUGUGAUCCACUGAGAUAUAAAGCCAAGAUGAAUAUCUUGGUUAUUUGUGUGAUGAUCUUCAUUAGUUGGAGUGUCCCUGCUGUUUUUGCAUUUGGAAUGAUCUUUCUGGAGCUAAACUUCAAAGGCGCUGAAGAGAUAUAUUACAAACAUGUUCACUGCAGAGGAGGUUGCUCUGUCUUCUUUAGCAAAAUAUCUGGGGUACUGACCUUUAUGACUUCUUUUUAUAUACCUGGAUCUAUUAUGUUAUGUGUCUAUUACAGAAUAUAUCUUAUCGCUAAAGAACAGGCAAGAUUAAUUAGUGAUGCCAAUCAGAAGCUCCAAAUUGGAUUGGAAAUGAAAAAUGGAAUUUCACAAAGCAAAGAAAGGAAAGCUGUGAAGACAUUGGGGAUUGUGAUGGGAGUUUUCCUAAUAUGCUGGUGCCCUUUCUUUAUCUGUACAGUCAUGGACCCUUUUCUUCACUACAUUAUUCCACCUACUUUGAAUGAUGUAUUGAUUUGGUUUGGCUACUUGAACUCUACAUUUAAUCCAAUGGUUUAUGCAUUUUUCUAUCCUUGGUUUAGAAAAGCACUGAAGAUGAUGCUGUUUGGUAAAAUUUUCCAAAAAGAUUCAUCCAGGUGUAAAUUAUUUUUGGAAUUGAGUUCAUAGAAUUAUUAUAUUUUACUGUUUUGCAAAUCGGUUGAUGAUCAUAUUUAUGAACACAACAUAACGAACCACAUGCACCAACCACAUGGAUUUUUUUUUAAAUCAGUUACUUGAGUCAAAGUAUGUAUGGUGAGUUAAAUUAUGAUGCUUAUAGGUAAUUUCCUAUUUGGGACAUAGUAGGUAUACGCUUUUCCAUUCUUACCACACAUAAUGGAACUUUGCAAAUCCAGUAUUUAAAGGCCUACAUUUUAUAUAACUUUUCCUGCCCUUAGAAGAACUGCCAUGAGUUUACUGUGGUACCUUAGUCAGCUGUUCAGUGGUGGAAACUAUAGGGCUGAAUUUGAGGAUGCAAAUCAGAAUGAUUUUGUCAUAUACGUAUACAUGUCCUGGUCACAUAUGUGUAUAAGUCUUUUAGUAAAAUCAACUAAAAGUACACACAUUAAAUGUUACCGCUAAAUAAUUGUUGACACAUAAUUUAUUUGUAUUGUUAAUAUAUAUUCCAAUCCUUAAAUAUCUUGAUCUUCACAUUUUUAAAUUAUGUUUUUCUGAUUCUCAUGCUUCUAAGAAAUUUGAAAAAUAAAGGAAAAUAUAAAAAUAAAAUAUAUACAAACCAAAUGAAAUUAAAAAAAUGUUAUUCAUAGUAUACUUCCUGGUAAGGAUUAUAUCAUCUAAAAUUCUUUAUUUUAUAUUAAUAUUUCUCUUUUUCAACUUUUAUUUUGGAGUCGGGGCAUAUGUGCACAUAUUAACUAAAUAUAAUGCAUGAUGCUGAGGUUUGAGCUAUGAGUAAUCCCUUUUUGUGGCUGUAUAACGUGACUGCACAGAUGUACAAAUAUAUUUUUAACCAUUCCCUAUUGUUAAUUCCAGUUGUUUCUAACUUUUCUAAAAAUAAUAUAAAUUAAAUGAAAUUCCUGCUUUUUACCUGCCACUGAAGUCAUGAAAAUGUCUAGAAGGAUUUUACCAUGUCUUAAGGUCAUAUCUGGCAUGAUAGGGUUCAAAACACAGGCUACCUGGUAUUAAACAAAUUCACUUUGCUGGGCUCCACAAUACACAGAAGGAGAAGCAGUCAUCCAUCAAAGUAGCUAAACAUGAGGGCCAACAAGAAGUAUAAUCAGACUAGAUGUACCAUGGCUAUUUAGAUGGCAUAUAUAAAAAUACAAAAGAGGAACAAAUAAUGGUUUCAAAUAAGAUUCUCUAAAGGAAGUGGGCAAACAUUCUAAAUUACAAGCAUUCAUCAGCAAUUGAGCUGAUGAAUACAAACUUCACAUGGUCUGUUUCAGAUUGAGUAUCACUGGGGAUUUGGAUUUACCUUCUGCUCAUGAAUAAGUUAGGGUAAGGCAAAUGAUUUUAAACGUAACUAAAUGCACACUGCUGCGUAUAAAUUUCUGUUUACAAAUCUGAGGAUCUCCGGAGGAUAUGUGAAAUCCUUCCAGAAAUUAUAGUCUGUUUCUGGAGUAUAUAUUUUGUUUCAAUGAUCUGUAUCAAUUUUUGCUCUAGUACUUUUAAAAACAUUAUGUUUUAUGUUUUUAAUUUAGUACACACAAGACUAAAUAAGUAGUGUCCCUAAUCACUCUCAGUUUCAAAAGAGUUUUUUUCACCUGUGAGACCAGUUUGACUUUUUUCACCUGUGAGUCCAGUCUGUCAAAUUUUAAAAAGGAAACAAGCAUUUAGUGAGUUU